GGUGCGCUUGAGAAGCGAUGGCGGCGGCCUGAACUCACCUAACACCGCAGCAGCAACCGGGCCCGGCCAGGUUCGGCGUUCCGUGAGUGAACGGUACGCAUGGGCCAGAGGGCCUGGAGAGUCGUUUGUGGGGAUGAGAGACUGGGAAAAGACGGUGACGGGUUUGGUUACUGUACUGGUUGUGAGGGGUUGGCAGGUGGUGAGGGUCCGGGUGUGAGUGUCUAAGAUAGGGAAGGAGGGUGAGAGCUUACAGGUGAGUGGACAAAUGAGGGGCUGUGAGAGGCUGGGUGCUUUCGGAGGUGCCAAGUUGAAGGGACUCCUGAACGCGGUUUACUAGGGCUGGGGCUACUGAGGGCUGGUGUGAAGGAUACCCUGGGACUAGAGUGAGGGGUAAGGCCUGCGCGAGGAGAGAGAGAGUAAAAGGCGCAGGUGGGAGCCUGCGGGGUGGCGGCAAAUUGGUGAGGGAGUUGAAGGCGAGGCAUGGGAGGAGGGAAUUAGGGCUUGUGAGACUUGGAUAAAGGUGAGAGGUUGGUUCUGAGGCCUCCUUCGAUGGACUGCCCUGUCCAGUGAGAGCAAUAGUUUUAGACAAAGUAGGGCAGCUUAGAUGGAAGUGUUGUGCACCUGACUCCUCUGCUCCCAUGGACUUUCCAUAUUCUGGAGGACGAGAAAAUGAAGGUGUCAUAGGCAAUAGUACUAUGGUAAUGAAAGUCAUAUUUGAGGCUCAGACUUCAACAGAGUAAUCACAGAAACUUCAGUUCCUUCGAGUUCCUUCUCUGGACUGCAUAGUUGAAGAUGGGCCCUCUCAUGAAGGGUUUUGCGCUGUGACAGCUUGUGUUUUCUCUCUACUUGCUUCUGGACAACCUUAUUCCACUGUUGCUCCUUACCUGUGCUUAACUGUGGGUCUUUGAUUGGAUUGACCAUAUUCAGUUGCUAAUUCUACUUUUAUGGAGGUCAUAUGGUUUGCCCUAUACAGUACUAUAUUUAGGAUCCCAAACAGGAUGGCCUUACUCUCCUUUCUUACAGUUGAAUUUUUUAAAAAGCUAGUUUAUAUUAUAUUUAAAAUGUGUGUUUGAUGAGUUUUGACAUGUGUACACAUCUGUGAAAUCAUCAUCAGUCUCAAGAUACUGAACAUUUUAGCCACCUGAAAAUUUAUCUCUUCCUCUCCACACCCUGUAGUUGGGUUCAUCUUACUAGCAUUCUUUUAGGUCCUCUUCUCCCCACCAACCCAAAUGCACGUGAAAUUCUGGAAAGUUGGUUUGGCAUUCAGUGAUAAUGGCCACUUUCACACUACUAAAUUUUCCUCUCUACUGCUAGUCAGCCAUGGGGUUGGGACAUCCUAUUCUUUCCAGACUCAGAAAGAGUUAAGUCUUUCCUUAACUCUACAGUGGACAGGGAGAGACCAUUUCCUGAGAAUUAGACAGCCUCAGUCCCCAUUCUUUUCCAGAGUCUUAGCUUCAGAGCCAACUCCUAUAUCCUGUGGUAUAUUCUCAUUGCUUCUUUCUGGAGUCCAGACAGGCCUCCAUAUUGGUAGAACACUUGGCAACUUGCCCAGUCAGUCAGAACUUACAGUUCAGAGUUUAGAGUAGUGGUUCCUAAACACUGGACCAAGGACCCUGUACAUGAUAAAAUUAUCAUCUAUCCAAGAUGGAGGGAGAGAAAGACAGUAUGGUUAUUCAUGAAGAUAAAUUUAUUCUCAGAGAUUAUCAUUCCUAUUCUUUUGGUGUUGCAGUGCUCUUUCGUUGAUGCAGUAAUGGUAACAGUAGAUGGUGGGUUAAAAAAAAAAAGAUCUAAUUUACCCAAAUAAAAAGUGUCAACCCAAUUUUUAAUUUUAAAAAUUAUUUCUAUAGCUUUAUGAACUUCAGAAAUUUAAAGUGAUGAUGGUGUGGCUGUUGUAUUAGGUUGAGGAAGCAUACAUUUAUACAAUGAUUCUGUAUAACUUAACAUCUGAACAGCAUUCAUGCUUUACAUAGGGAUUUCAAAUUUUAUUAUACUGAUUUAUAUAGAUACCUUGUAGACAAAGACAGGAACUUUCAUUUUAUAGAUGAGAAAUUAAAUUCAGUAGCCAGAGAUCAUACAGGGAUACAGUGGCAAGGCUGAACCCAGAAUUUUGUCUCAGAGUGAGAGAGACUUUGGGAAAGAAGAUUUAUAAUAGACACUGAAGGUGAUGUGGGAGGAUUUUUUAAUGAUUUGUAAUUGUUCUAUUUCCAAAAGACAGAAAAGGGACUGUGAGAGUGACAUAGGGAUGAAGGUUAUGUUUAAUGCUGUCGCAGUGACAUUGGAACAGGUAUAUAUAAUACCUGGAUCACAUCUUGAUAGUGGAUCAUAUCAUGAUAGUGAUAGGAUGAAUCAAAUCAAAUAUUAGAUGGUUCUUAGGGACUGUCUAAAUCCUUGUUAUAAUGGAGAAAGCACUGGAUUUGGUAAGCUUAUUGUUUGCUAUCCCAAACUCUGUUGAAAUAGUAGUGCAUUAAGUAUAAUGGAUUUUGAUUUGUAUCAUAUAGUGAGUGGUAGUUCUGAGAGGAUGAAACAUACAUGAGGAUGAUGAUGUAGAGAUAGAAACAUGUUUAGGGUACUGUGUUAAUCAUUUAUUCCAUAUCUGCUCUGUGCCAGGCACUCUACUAAGUGCUAGGAGAAUGAAUUCGUUUAUUCAUUCAACAAAUACUUCUUCAACAUAUAGUCUGUGCUUGUGAUGCUCACAUUUUAUGGGAUAACAACAUGAAUAAAACAUGGUCAUCCGAGCUCUCAAGGGAUUUUCAGUCUAGUAGGGAGAGAGAGACACAUGAAAACAUAAUUUCAAUUUAGAGAGAUAAUGUGAAAUGUGAAAAUAUAUCAUAAUAGGCUGGGCGUAGUGGCUCACGCCUAGCAUUUUGGGAGGCUGAGGCAGGCAGAUCGCUUGACUUCAGGAGUUUGAGACCAACCUGGGCAACAUUUUGAAACCCUGCCUCUACCAAAACAACAACAACAACGACAAUAAAACCACCACCAAAAAAACCCACCAAAAAUUAGCCAGGUGUGGUUGCACAUACUUGUGGUCCUGGCUACUCCGGAGGCUGAGGUGGGAGGAUUGCUUGAGCCUGGGAGGCAGAGGUUGCAGUGAGAUGAGGUCACACCACUGCACUUCAGCCUGGGUGACAGAGGCCCCACCUCAAGAAAAAAAAAAAAAAAAAAAAGAAAAUAUAUCAUAAUGAGUUGAUUACUCCUUUGUAUCUAGUGUCAUCUUUCCCUGUAUUCCAAGUAUACAUGUUUAUUGAUCUGUGUAUCUCCACAAGUAUCUCAAAAUUAACAUGUCCAAAACAGAAUUCAUAGUCUUUGCCCCAAAAGCCCGACUUUGCCCUCAUAUCCCCUAUCUCACUCCAGGCAAGGACUACAUUGUCAUCUUUCAUACUUUCUGCUCUUUUACUCCCUGCAUUCAAUCAUUUGCUAGAAUCUUAAUACAUUUCGCUCUGUGUUAUCUCUCUUCUCUAUAUCUCCAUUGCUACAUCUUCACUGUCAAAGCUUUAGUUUAGCUCCCCCUCACCUCAUAUGAUUUUUUUAAAACAAUUUUUUGUCUUAAAACUUGCUAUUUUCUGGUCCAUCCCUAGAAUGAUUUUUCUGAAAAUACACAUCUGAUCUCCGAACUCCUUGGCUUAAAAACUUUUGGCUCUUUGUGUCCUGUAGGACAACAUCCAAAUUUCUUAAUAUGGCAUCAUUUAGCUUCAGCUUACCUCUCCAGUCUCGUGUGCCACUCCCUAGUCUGUAUUCUAGUUUGAAUAAAUUGUUCACAGUUCCCUAAAACCAUGCUGCUUUUUUGAGCCUUGAAAUCUUUGUAAUAGCUGCUUCCUCUACUAGGAAUGCCUUUUCUUCUCUGCCCAGUGAACUUUCCUUAUCCUUUAGGAUCUAGUUCAGUUUCACCUCCUUUUUGACAUCUCUGUCAAGGUAGAGAUAACUGUGUGUGACAUGAGGAUUCAUUGCUGUAAAGAGGAGUCACUGUAGAAUAGAGGUUCACUUUUGUGAAUUGGAUGGACCCCGCUGGAGUCAGAUGAGGAGAUCCCUGCAAGAAGCAGAAGUGAUAUUGCGGGGAGGGAAGGGAAUGAGUUGGGACCAUACCCUGACAUCCCAUUUGUCUGAGGGAUGGAAAAGCAGGGAAGAAAUGUGUAAGCUGAGCUCUAGUAUAAAUUCCUAGUAGGUGGUGUUUUUGGUUGGUUGGUUUUUCCCUUUGUAUUUCUAUGAGAUUUUAAUCAGGUCAUUCAACUUCCAGUAUUUAGGGUAACAGCCCAUUCAUCCUCCUUAUGUCAGUAAUUAGUCUUCUUGCCUAGGAAGAGCCACUGUAAGGAGAGAGACACCACAGAAUUUUACUGACCUGUUCUUGGAAGAUCAUUUUGGUCUCUCUGUCCAAUGUAGGUGUUGCAGGUAUAUCCCUUCCCCCAGCUCCCUCCUCUUUGCCUCUCCCAGGGCAAAGGUUCAUAAGUGAGGCUGAGCCACUUCCUGCCCUGUAUCUGCAGUUCCGAGGUUGGUUGUCACCCUUGCUGUGUGUGGCUGUAAGGCUGUAUUUUGGGCUAUAAGAUUUAGAAAUCUGGACUGGCCAGUGACCUCUGGGCUUGCCAUUCCAGCCUGGUAUAACCUCUGGCUCCAUGGGCAGCUACUGGCUCCUACAGACCGGAUGAAGCAGACUGGAGACACAAGUGGAGAAAACCUCCAGCUGGCAAAUCCUCAGAGUGUAGGCCUCUGGCUGCCAGUCCUGCCCAGCCUGCCUCAUGGAGAGGAUGAAUUGGCUGAGCAGACUGGCCUCCCGGGGCCCUGGGCACCGUAUACCUCAAGGGGCCAAUCUCCAAACCCCAGUCAUGGCUGAUCCCGAGACCUGCCUCAUGGUCUUCAAGAAUCACUGGUCCCAGGUGGUGCGAAUCCUGGAGCGGCAAGGCCCUCGGGCAGCUCCUGGGGGUGCAGACGAUCUCAGUGCUGUGCGCAACCACACUUACCAGAUGUUGACACUGCUGGCAGAGGACCGUGCAGUUCCCUCGGCCCCCACAGGCCCUGGGCCCCUGCUGGAGUUUGCUCUGCACGAGGAUCUGCUGACCCGUGUGUUGACAUGGCAGCUGCAAUGGGAUGAGCUUGGGGAUGGGGUCGAGGAACGGCGGGCUGAGCAACUGAAACUAUUUGAAAUGCUAGUGAGCGAAGCUCGCCAGCCACUGUUGCGGCAUGGUCCAGUUCGUGAGGCUCUGCUCACCCUGCUGGAUGCCUGUGGCCGCCCUGUGCCCAGUAGCCCAGCACUGGAUGAAGGCUUGGUGCUACUUCUCAGCCAGCUGUGUGUUUGUGUGGCCCAGGAGCCUUCAUUGCUCGAGUUCUUCCUGCAGCCACCUCCUGAGCCUGGAGCCGCUCCCCGUCUUCUUCUCUUUUCUCGCCUUGUCCCUUUUGUGCAUCGAGAGGGCACCCUGGGCCAGCAGGCCCGUGAUGCCCUACUUCUUCUCAUGGCUUUGUCAGCUGGGAGCCCCACUGUGGGCCGCUACAUCGCGGAUCACUCUUACUUCUGCCCGGUGCUGGCCACAGGGCUCAGUGCCCUGUACUCAUCACUGCCUCGAAAGAUUGAGGUUCCAGGGGAUGAUUGGCACUGUCUGCGACGGGAAGACUGGCUGGGAGUGCCAGCCCUUGCACUCUUCAUGAGUUCCCUGGAGUUCUGCAAUGCAGUAAUUCAGGUGGCUCACCCCCUGGUGCAGAAGCAGUUGGUUGAUUAUAUCCAUAAUGGGUUCCUGGUGCCUGUCAUGGGUCCUGCCUUGCACAAGACCUCUGUGGAGGAGAUGAUCGCCAGUACCGCCUAUCUGGAACUUUUCCUACGGAGUAUCUCAGAGCCUGCUUUGCUCCGUACCUUCCUGCGAUUCCUGUUGUUGCACCGGCAUGACACCCACACCAUCCUCGACACCCUCGUUGCUCGUAUUGGCAGUAACUCCCGGCUCUGCAUGGUCUCUCUGAGUCUCUUCAGGACCCUCCUGAACCUCAGCUGUGAGGAUGUCCUGCUGCAGCUGGUUCUCAGGUAUCUUGUUCCAUGUAACCACGUUAUGCUGAGCCAGAAGCCGGCUGUUCGUGAUGUGGACCUAUAUGGACGAGCAGCUGACAAGUUUCUCUCCCUAAUCCCACGCUGUUGUCGGCACCACGCCCCCAGCCCACCUCGUCCAGAGCAUGCCUCAUGGGCACGAGGUGGGCCUAGCAGAGAGACAGGGAGAAGGGAGGACAUCACGGGUCCUGGAAGCCCAAGUGUGGACUCCUCUUCUGUGACGACAGUACCCCGGCCCUCCACACCAUCUCGUCUGGCUCUCUUCCUGCGGCAGCAGAGCCUGGGUGGCUCUGAGUCUCCAGGCCCAGCCCCUUGCUCACCAGGGCUUUCUGCAUCCCCCGCCUCCAGCCCUGGCCGACGGCCUACCCCUGCAGAGGAGCCUGGAGAGCUGGAAGACAAUUACCUGGAGUAUCUGCGUGAGGCACGUCGUGGUGUGGACCGCUGUGUCCGAGCCUGCCGUACCUGGUCUGCCCCCUAUGAUGGCGAGCGGCCCUCUCCUGAGCCCAGUCCUUUUGGCUCCCGGACUAAGAAACGCAGCCUACUGCCUGAGGAGGACAGGAACAACGUGGGGGAAGGGGAGGAGGAAGAGCUGGGGAGGAGGGGGCGGGCUGGGGGUGCAGGGGAGGGCCCUGGUCACCUGCCCCCUCCCCAGCUCAAUGGAGUGCCAGGAUCAUGGCCUGAGGGGGCCAAGAAGGUUCGUCUGGUGCCAAAGGAGGGAGCUGGGGAACUGCUAGAGGGCAUCUCCGAGGGCAUGGCAGGACUAGAGGGCUUUGGGCAGGAGCUCCGGGAGCUAGAGGUGGCAUUGAGCAAUGGGGGAACUGGCUCAGAGUCCCCCUUAGAACCUCCACUGCCCCUUGAGGAGGAGGAGGCCUACGAGAGCUUCACCUGUCCCCCUGAGCCCCCUGGCCCCUUCCUCAGCAGCCCUUUGCGGACUCUCAACCAGCUGCCAAGCCAGCCCUUCACUGGCCCCUUCAUGGCUGUGCUCUUUGCCAAACUCGAGAACAUGCUGCAGAACUCCGUCUAUGUCAACUUCCUGCUGACGGGGCUGGUGGCCCAGCUGGCCUGUCACCCCCAGCCCCUGCUCCGCUCUUUCCUGCUCAACACCAACAUGGUCUUCCAGCCCAGUGUCAAGUCCCUGCUGCAGGUGCUGGGCUCUGUGAAGAAUAAGAUUGAGAACUUUGCGGCUUCCCAGGAGGACUUCCCAGCACUGCUGUCCAAAGCCAAGAAGUACCUCAUUGCCCGUGGCAAGUUGGACUGGGCUGAGGGCCCUGCAGCAGGACCUGCCCCACGCCGUUCUGAUCCCCUAGUGAAGAGCCGGAGGCCAUCCUUGGGGGAGUUACUCCUGCGGCAUGCACACAGUCCAACCAGGGCCCGGCAGGCGGCACAAUUGGUCCUUCAGCCUGGGCGAGACGGAGCAGGACUUGGCCUAAGUGGGGGCUCCCCUGGGGCUUCAACUCCAGUUCUACUCACCCGGGGCGGGGCCCCUGAACGCCAAGGUGAGGCUCUUCGAGUCAAGAAUGCUGUCUACUGUGCAGUCAUUUUCCCUGAAUUUCUCAAGGAGUUGGCUGCCAUCUCCCAGGCUCAUGCCGUCACCUCGCCUUUCUUGUUGGAGACUUCAGAGGAAGGAUCUGGCCCUCUCAUCUCAGGCUGUGGGCCCCUCAAUCCUUAACUUUCUUCCAUGGACAAUCAGGGCCAUGGGUGGCCCGGGCUGGGGCUAGGGCACAGGCUCCUUUUUAUGUUUGGAGGCAGUGGCAAAAGGACUUUUUAAUUUAUUUCAGAUGAAUGUUUUAUGGAGAACUUGUUGCAAUAUGUAUAAAAGGGAAAUCUCUA